UUAUUUUAAAAUUUUAUUUAUUUUUGUUUUGGGGACAGGGUCUCCUCCUGUCACCCAGGCUGGAUUGCAAUGGCACAAUCAUAGCUCACUGCAGCCUGGAACUCCCUGGCUCAAGCGAUCCUCCUGCCUCCAAUUCCCAAAGAGCUGAGAUUAUAGGCAUGAACCACUGCAACUCACCCAAAUCCAAGUUUAUACUAAAAGAUAAAAUUCCAACAUUUCAGAGAAAAUGAAAGUCACAAAGUUAUCCCAGUCUCUGAAGUCACUGUCAAAACUUUGGUGAGGAAUCUUCCAGGUUUUCCCCUACUUAAAAUAUAUAUUAAUAUUAUGUAAGUAAUAUUAGCGGCAUUUUCACCCAGGCUGGAGUGCAGUGGCACGAUCUCAGCUCACUGCAACCUCCACCUCCCGGGUUCAAGCAAUCCUCCUGCCUCAGCCUCCCGAGUAGCUGGGACUACAGGCGCCGGCCACCAUGCCUGGCUAAUUUUUGUAUUUUCAGUGGAGACAGGGUUUCACCAUAUUGACCAGGCUGAUCUCGAACUCCUGACCUCAGGUGAUCUGCCCACCUUGGCCUUCCAAAGUUCUGGGAUUACAGGCGUGAGCCACUGGGCCCAGCCUCCUUAACCUUUUAAAAAAGGUUAAAAGUAUGCUGGGCACUUCUUUUCAUAGCAAUACUUAAAAGCGAUCUUACUCUUUUUAAUGACUGUAUAGAAUUUUAUAAUAUAACUCUUCUUUGGGAGACAAUUGAAAUGUUCUUUAUCUUCACUGUGGUAGUGGAGAUGUGGGUGUGUACAACAGCUAAAAUUCAACAAGUUGAACACUUUAAAUAGAUGCAGUUUAUUGCAUGCAAAGUAUGUCCCAAUAUGAUGAUUUAAAAAUAUUAUCGUCUUUGAGAUUUGUACUUUGCUUAUGUGAAACAAAACAAAACAAAAACCCUGUUCUUGUGCCCAGGAGACACACCCUGACUCAUCUGGAGGUAGAGGGUCAUGCUGUCUGCAACUUACCCUCACAGGCUCUGAAAUAACAAUAAUAGCAGUAUAUUUACAGAUUCAGAAAGAGAGAAAGCUAUAGUAAAAAUGUUCAUAAGUAAAACUAGAUAAAGGUCAAAAAUAAAUAAUAAAACUACGUCUUUUAAAUUUUAUCUCUCCUUUACUUUUUCUCUCCCCUUUUCUUCCUAUCUCUUCCCUCCUUUCUUAACACGUUCCCCUAUCCUUCCCUCCUUUCACCACUCUCUGCACUUGAUCCCCGGUGUAUUCCAGCCCCCAGGCCAACACACUUCACCGCGUCCGCCUGGGGCAGGUCAGAGAAGGGACGCGAGGCGGCGCUGUCACAGCAUUCUAUGCGCCCCAGCGCCCUGGGCCGCGCAGGUCUUUUAUCAUUUCAGUGGUCACUCCCGUCUUUGACGGGGCCACACUCGGGGUGUAAAUUAGGAUCCUCACUGAAGCGGCGGGACCCUGAGAGGCUUUUUCCUGGCCCCUUAGUUGUGGGUUUUCCUGCGGGCGGUGGAGUCCGUUUCCAUCAGAACCGCCCAGAGGCGGGCGCUGCCUUCCAGGGGUGAAGCGUUUUCGGACCCUGGAAUCUGUGGGCGGCCUGCGGGAGGGGCUGAGGCGCAGUUCCCUACUCACUCAGAUCCGAAUCCACCGCGGUGCUGUUUCCAGCGAGUCAGAUUCCAGAUCGCGCUCCAGCCUGGACUCGGAAUUCCUGCCCCGCGGGUCUGCAUUUUCACAGCGGCAGGUGUGAGUGCCGCGCAGCUGGAGACCAGAAGCCUGAGGCAGCUCGGCCCUCCCCAGCCCAAAGUGCCGUUAUUCCGUUUCUGUAUCAGUAAACACGUUUCAUUUUUCGGAGACCAGGGAAGGGUGAUGGGUGAUCCCAGUCCUCGCAGUGAAUUCCGGGCCACAAAAUUCAAAACGCUUGCUGGCAAAGCCGUGCGCGGUGGCUCAAGCCUGUAAUUCCAGCACUUUGGGAGGCCGAGGCGGGCGGAUCACCUGAGGUCGGGAUUUCCAGACCAGCCUGACCAACAUAGAGAAACCCCGCCUCUACUAAAAAUACAAAAUUAGCCGGGGGUGGCGCAUGCCUGUAAUCCCAGCUAGUCGGGAGGCUGAGGCAGGAGACUCACUUGAACCCGGGAGGCGGAGGUUGCUGUGAGCCGAGAUCGCGCCACUGCACUCCAGCCUGGGCAACAAGAGCGAAACUCCGUUUCAAAAAAAAACAAAAAACAAAAAGCUUUCGGGCGCCGAGGGCAGCCCCGCCCUGAAUUUUGUGAGCGCCCGCGCUGGGCCGUUUCUCUUUCUUUUCCGGACCCUGCAGUGGCGCCUAAAGUCUGCGAGGAGGAAGUCGCCUCUGUGCUCAGCCCCACAGUCUUCGUUACAACCUCAUGGUGCUGUCCCAGGAUGGAUCUGUGCAGUCAGGGUUUCUCGCUGAGGGACAUCUGGAUGGUCAGCCCUUCCUGCGCUAUGACAGGCAGAAACGCAGGGCAAAGCCCCAGGGACAGUGGGCAGAAGAUGUCCUGGGAGCUGAGACCUGGGACACAGAGACCGAGGACUUGACAGAGAAUGGGCAAGACCUCAGGAGGACCCUGACUCAUAUCAAGGACCAGAAAGGAGGCUUGCAUUCCCUCCAGGAGAUUAGGGUCUGUGAGAUCCAUGAAGACAGCAGCACCAGGGGCUCCCGGCAUUUCUACUACAAUGGGGAGCUCUUCCUCUCCCAAAACCUGGAGACUCAAGAAUCGACAGUGCCCCAGUCCUCCAGAGCUCAGACCUUGGCUAUGAACGUCACAAAUUUCUGGAAGGAAGAUGCCAUGAAGACCAAGACACACUAUCGCGCUAUGCAGGCAGACUGCCUGCAGAAACUACAGCGAUAUCUGAAAUCCGGGGUGGCCAUCAGGAGAACAGUGCCCCCCAUGGUGAAUGUCACCUGCAGCGAGGUCUCAGAGGGCAACAUCACCGUGACAUGCAGGGCUUCCAGCUUCUAUCCCCGGAAUAUCACACUGACCUGGCGUCAGGAUGGGGUAUCUUUGAGCCACAACACCCAGCAGUGGGGGGAUGUCCUGCCUGAUGGGAAUGGAACCUACCAGACCUGGGUGGCCACCAGGAUUCGCCAAGGAGAGGAGCAGAGGUUCACCUGCUACAUGGAACACAGCGGGAAUCACGGCACUCACCCUGUGCCCUCUGGGAAGGCGCUGGUGCUUCAGAGUCAACGGACAGACUUUCCAUAUGUUUCUGCUGCUAUGCCAUGUUUUGUUAUUAUUAUUAUUCUCUGUGUCCCUUGUUGCAAGAAGAAAACAUCAGCGGCAGAGGGUCCAGAGCUUGUGAGCCUGCAGGUCCUGGAUCAACACCCAGUUGGGACAGGAGACCACAGGGAUGCAGCACAGCUGGGAUUUCAGCCUCUGAUGUCAGCUACUGGGUCCACUGGUUCCACUGAGGGCGCCUAGACUCUACAGCCAGGCGGCCAGGAUUCAACUCCCUGCCUGGAUCUCACCAGCACUUUCCCUCUGUUUCCUGACCUAUGAAACAGAAAAUAACAUCACUUAUUUAUUGUUGUUGGAUGCUGCAAAGUGUUAGUAGGUAUGAGGUGUUUGCUGCUCUGCCACGUAGAGAGCCAGCAAAGGGAUCAUGACCAACUCAACAUUCCAUUGGAGGCUAUAUGAUCAAACAGCAAAUUGUUUAUCAUGAAUGCAGGAUGUGGGCAAACUCACGACUGCUCCUGCCAACAGAAGGUUUGCUGAGGGCAUUCACUCCAUGGUGCUCAUUGGAGUUAUCUACUGGGUCAUCUAGAGCCUAUUGUUUGAGGAAUGCAGUCUUACAAGCCUACUCUGGACCCAGCAGCUGACUCCUUCUUCCACCCCUCUUCUUGCUAUCUCCUAUACCAAUAAAUACGAAGGGCUGUGGAAGAUCAGAGCCCUUGUUCACGAGAAGCAAGAAGCCCCCUGACCCCUUGUUCCAAAUAUACUCUUUUGUCUUUCUCUUUAUUCCCACGUUCGCCCUUUGUUCAGUCCAAUACAGGGUUGUGGGGCCCUUAACAGUGCCAUAUUAAUUGGUAUCAUUAUUUCUGUUGUUUUUGUUUUUGUUUUUGUUUUUGUUUUUGAGACAGAGUCUCACUCUGUCACCCAGGCUGCAGUUCACUGGUGUGAUCUCAGCUCACUGCAACCUCUGCCUCCCAGGUUCAAGCACUUCUCGUACCUCAGACUCCCGAAUAGCUGGGAUUACAGACAGGCACCACCACACCCAGCUAAUUUUUGUAUUUUUUGUAGAGACGGGGUUUCGCCAAGUUGACCAGCCCAGUUUCAAACUCCUGACCUCAGGUGAUCUGCCUGCCUUGGCAUCCCAAAGUGCUGGGAUUACAAGAAUGAGCCACCGUGCCUGGCCUAUUUUAUUAUAUUGUAAUAUAUUUUAUUAUAUUAGCCACCAUGCCUGUCCUAUUUUCUUAUGUUUUAAUAUAUUUUAAUAUAUUACAUGUGCAGUAAUUAGAUUAUCAUGGGUGAACUUUAUGAGUGAGUAUCUUGGUGAUGACUCCUCCUGACCAGCCCAGGACCAGCUUUCUUGUCACCUUGAGGUCCCCUCGCCCCGUCACACCGUUAUGCAUUACUCUGUGUCUACUAUUAUGUGUGCAUAAUUUAUACCGUAAAUGUUUACUCUUUAAAUAGA